GGAGACUUCGGGCCCGGCUGGCGGGCGGCGCCGGGAGCGCGGGGGCGGCGGGCCCGGGUCGAGCAUGUAGCGGCUGCUGGCGGCGGGGCUCCCGGGGCGGGCCGGGCGGGCCGCGGGAGCCGCACGCGGCGAUAUGGAAGAGGAGGGCAAGAAGGGCAAGAAGCCUGGAAUUGUCUCGCCAUUUAAACGAGUAUUCCUAAAAGGUGAAAAGAGUAGAGAUAAGAAAGCCCAUGAGAAGGUGACAGAGAGGCGCCCUCUGCACACUGUGGUGUUGUCAUUGCCUGAGCGCGUCGAGCCAGACAGACUGCUGAGCGACUAUAUUGAGAAGGAGGUAAAGUAUUUAGGUCAGUUAACGUCCAUACCAGGAUACCUGAAUCCCUCCAGUAGGACUGAAAUCCUGCAUUUCAUAGACAAUGCAAAGAGAGCCCACCAGCUUCCGGGACACUUGACUCAGGAGCACGAUGCUGUGCUCAGCCUGUCUGCGUACAACGUCAAGCUGGCCUGGAGGGACGGGGAGGAUAUCAUCCUCAGGGUGCCCAUCCAUGACAUCGCCGCCGUCUCCUAUGUUCGGGAUGACGCUGCACACCUGGUGGUCCUGAAGACAGCCCAGGACCCAGGGAUCUCCCCCAGCCAGAGUCUGUGUGCGGAAAGUUCCAGAGGCCUCAGUGCAGGCUCCCUGUCGGAGAGUGCAGUUGGGCCCGUGGAGGCAUGCUGCCUGGUCAUCCUGGCUGCAGAGAGCAAGGUCGCUGCGGAGGAGCUUUGCUGUCUGCUAGGCCAGGUCUUCCAGGUUGUUUACACGGAGUCCACCAUCGACUUUCUGGACAGAGCGAUAUUUGAUGGGGCCUCUACCCCGACCCACCACCUGUCCCUGCACAGCGGACCAUGGCCAGACCCAUGGGAAGCUGCUCAGGCUGCCCUGGGAGGCCAGCUGGCAGUGGUGGAGCAGUGGCAGAUGGGGAAGAAUGGAAGGUACCCCAGAGCUGUCUCUUCCUGCAUGGCCCACACAGCAUUUUCAGGAGUCUGUUAGUCCAUUGAAAACACUUCAUCAGCAAGCUCACUUGAGUUAAGUCUUCAAAAACAUCAUCUGUUUUUCAGAUGUAUUACUUAUUGAGGAUUAAUGGGUUAUAUAAAUUGAGGUGCAUAAAAAGCUGUUGGAGGCUGGGUGUGGUGGCUCAUGCCUGUAAUCCCAGCACUUUGGGAGGCUGAGGCGGGCGGAUCACCUGAGGUCGGGAGUUCAAGACCAGCCUGACCAACAUGGAGAAACCCUGUCUCUACUAAAAAAUACCAAGAAAAAAAAAAAGGCUGUUGGAAACAGUGCGGCUUGUUGAGUACAAUUUCUUCUUUUUACGGAGAUAAGUCCCAGCCCUCUGCCCUUUCCCCAGUAACUCGCACAUCUCAGUGAAGAGAGUAAAUGGUGGAGAAGCCUGUGCUGGUGUGAGGGCUGCUCCUCAGUGCCUCCUUCUUCCCUUUCUUGCUGCUGGUGCCAGAGCCCUUUGUGGGCACUACACGCCUUGUGUUGGCCCAGCAGCUGCAGAGAGACAGCUGCUGAGCUCUCAGGCAUCCUCUCUAUCUCAUUUAGUCCUCGGUGGCCCAGCGAGAUAGGUGCAAUCUUCAUCCCCAUUUUAGAGAUGGGGAAGUGGAGGCUUAGAAGUCAACAGCUUAUCCAGAGGAAUGUACCAUAUGAGUAGCAGAUGAUUUAUCGAGCUGUAAUUAAACAUUCAGUUUUAGUGCGACUGGUUUGGCCCUUGUGCUUUAAAAUUCCCAAAGGGCCUUUUUUUCUUUAAUAAUUUUUUUUUUACUGAGAAGUACACAAGUCAUACAUGUACAGUUGAAUGAAUUUUCAUAAAGUAAACACAUCAUGUAACACCACUACUGGGGGUUGCUGAAGUGGGCUUCUUCCCCUGCCAGCCUUUCCCAAGACCUCCCCGUGGGAUCCACACACAGAUGUGCACACGUUACGCACAUGCAUGCAUUCUCUGCUUAUUUCUGCCUUGGAGUUUUGCUUGCUGUGUUCUCUCUACUACAGCUAUGCCAAAACAUAGCAGCAUAAACAGCAGAAAUAUAUUCUCUUAUAAUUCUAUACGUUAAGAGUCCAUUGUGGGUCCCACUGGGCUAAAGUUGAGGUGUCCACAGGGCUGGUUCCUUCUGGAGGCUCCAGAGAAGAAGCCAUUUCCUUGUCUUUCCAGCUCCUAAAGGCGGCUGCAUGCCUUGGCUCAUGGCCCUUCCUCUGUCUUCACAGCCAGCCACGUGACCUCUUCCACAGUCACAUCUUCCUUUGACUGUCAGCUUCCUCUGCAUUUCAGGACUCUUGCAAUCACAUUGAGCCCACCCAAAUUCUCCAGGGUCAUCUCCCUAUUUCAAG